ACAUACAUAUUCAGUGGUGAGUAAGAACAGAAGUGGAAAGCCUUACUUACCACAGUUUAUUAUAUGUUUCAUGCCUGUGAUAAUUACUUUUAUAAUGCCACUUGUGAAAAAAUUGAUCAGAUUAGGAUGAAUCACCUUGCUGGCCAACAGUUAUUGGAAUGAUUCUCCAUGUGUGACUUCGUUGCACUAUUACAAAAUGUGGCAGGAUAGACCUGCCCAGCCAUUGUUGCCGAUGUUCAUUUGUAAUGCUGCCUUAAGGAGAUGAGGAGAUGAGAGCCAAUUGUUCCAGCAGCUCAGCCUGCCCUGCCAACAGUUCAGAGGAGGAGCUGCCAGUGGGACUGGAGGUGCAUGGAAACCUGGAGCUCGUUUUCACAGUGGUGUCCACUGUGAUGAUGGGGCUGCUCAUGUUCUCUUUGGGAUGUUCCGUGGAGAUCCGGAAGCUGUGGUCGCACAUCAGGAGACCCUGGGGCAUUGCUGUGGGACUGCUCUGCCAGUUUGGGCUCAUGCCUUUUACAGCUUAUCUCCUGGCCAUUAGCUUUUCUCUGAAGCCAGUCCAAGCUAUUGCUGUUCUCAUCAUGGGCUGCUGCCCGGGGGGCACCAUCUCUAACAUUUUCACCUUCUGGGUUGAUGGAGAUAUGGAUCUCAGCAUCAGUAUGACAACCUGUUCCACCGUGGCCGCCCUGGGAAUGAUGCCACUCUGCAUUUAUCUCUACACCUGGUCCUGGAGUCUUCAGCAGAAUCUCACCAUUCCUUAUCAGAACAUAGGAAUUACCCUUGUGUGCCUGACCAUUCCUGUGGCCUUUGGUGUCUAUGUGAAUUACAGAUGGCCAAAACAAUCCAAAAUCAUUCUCAAGAUUGGGGCCGUUGUUGGUGGGGUCCUCCUUCUGGUGGUCGCAGUUGCUGGUGUGGUCCUGGCGAAAGGAUCUUGGAAUUCAGACAUCACCCUUCUGACCAUCAGUUUCAUCUUUCCUUUGAUUGGCCAUGUCACGGGUUUUCUGCUGGCACUUUUUACCCACCAGUCUUGGCAAAGGUGCAGGACAAUUUCCUUAGAAACUGGAGCUCAGAAUAUUCAGAUGUGCAUCACCAUGCUCCAGUUAUCUUUCACUGCUGAGCACUUGGUCCAGAUGUUGAGUUUCCCACUGGCCUAUGGACUCUUCCAGCUGAUAGAUGGAUUUCUUAUUGUUGCAGCAUAUCAGACGUACAAGAGGAGAUUGAAGAACAAACAUGGAAAAAAGAACUCAGGUUGCACAGAAGUCUGCCAUACGAGGAAAUCGACUUCUUCCAGAGAGACCAAUGCCUUCUUGGAGGUGAAUGAAGAAGGUGCCAUCACUCCUGGGCCACCAGGGCCAAUGGAUUGCCACAGGGCUCUCGAGCCAGUUGGCCACAUCACUUCAUGUGAAUAGCAGGGACUAGCUGGCUGGACUGGCCCCCUUCUUUUUCAGUGGCCAGUAAAGACAGUGUGCAGCUGACACAUGAAUCUUGUUGGUAGGGCCAGUGUGAAUAUUUAAGUGUUCAAUGUUAGAAUAUUUAUAUUUUCAUGUGGAUUGUGAAUUGUGAUGGGAUCACUUUUGGAGAUUCCCAUUUCAGGGAGUUUCUUCUGGGGGUUAACAUAACGUAUCAAUG